GGUGAUCAGCACAGCACUGGGCACUUUGCUGAUGGAAUUAAUUGAGCCAGCUUGGGUUGUCCAGCUCCAAGAUGCUCGCUUUGAGCUGUCAGAAAUGCUUGGGCUGGACCAGAGGACCAUUUUUUCUGCUAAUCACUUCCUGGAAAUCUUACCCUCAGGCAGGAUGUGCUGAAGCCCAAGCCAGUUUGUGGAUUUUUAAGUACUCAGAAAUUUUGCAAGCUUUUUGUGAAACCAUUAGUUUAUUGAAAUCAACUGUGGUAGCAGUAUUUAAACCACAGAAAUUACAAAGUUGGUAAAUGCUACGCUUUAGGGCUUUUUUUUUUUUUUUUAAAUCUUGUAGAGCUUGUUAACCAGAACACCACUGUAAGAGACCUUGAAUCUUUUUGUUCCCAGGACUUUCUGAAUUUUCAGCCCAUAUGACAUGGAAGAAGAGUUAGAAGGGGAAUCUGACUGCUUGGAUCAGGGACUGUCUGGCUGGUGGAACUUGAAUGUAUACAACACUCUUCAUUUGCAUGUUUUGACAUUUUAAAAAAUGUUUUCACUUUCCUUAUCUACUUUGACUCUAAUAACAUCCUGAAAGGUAAGUAGAAUUAUUCUCAUAAUAUGAUGAAGAACCCAAGGCUCUCAAGGGAACACCACUCUUGGAUUAUUUAGCCCCGCUCUUCUACAAGAAUUGCAUACCCCAACCCCUGGAGCCCCUCCCCAUAUCCAUGUUUCUGCCCUAUAAUCUGAUCCUUUCACCAAAAAUGUUUAGAUCAGGUACACACACCUGAACUAAAUUGGGACUAUCAGUUUCUCUCUCUUUAAAUUGCCCUGAGAAUUGAAACUCAGAGGAGCAAAAGUCUAAGUUUUGAGAGAUAACAUGUGUAAAAUGGCAGGAAUCCAAAUCCAUAGGCACAGUCCACAGAUUCCUGAAGCUAGGGGUUCUGGCCCGAACCUGGUUUUCAAUCUUCUCCCCUUAAGCCCUUCCUAGCUCUUUUAAACUCUUUGAAUUGCUUUAAAUAGCCCUAGUUUCUUAAACUAAAUUCUCCUUUUUUGGUAAAGGUACAUUGAAUUAGUUUCUGUUAUUUGCUAUCAAAAGAAUCUUACCUAAUAUGGGCACAGAGAUGUGAAGAUCUUUUUUCAAGGCUGCACAGCUAGUGAGCAACUGACCAGUUUUGAACCCAAGUCUGUCUGGCUCCAGGUAUAAUGCCUGAGUCCUUAUUCCAUAUACACUGGUUAGACUGGAGCUAUGAGUGGAAGUUUUUUUGUCCUGCCCAUUAUGAAAGUUGAAAAAUUCUCCUGAUAACUCCUGCCCCAUUCUUUAUAUUAAUACAUUCUCUUUUUUCUUAAGUCCAAUGAAGCCUAAUUUCGGAGAUAUAAUCAAGAUGAGCUGAGCUGAUUUAGGUUGAUCACAGGACAAAAUGAAGGAAAUAGGAAAAAUCUCUAGUUUUCCUUCUCUUCAAAGCUUAGACUCACUAACUUCAGAAGAGGUGUUAAAUGUCCUAAGAUUGUUAAUUUGGAUAUCUGUUGACCUAGGCUCACUCCCAAAUAGAAUUGGAUCAAGGAAAAAUGAAUCAAACCUGUCCUGAGGUUUUUCUCUCCUCCUCCCCGAGAGUGCCCCAUGCCUCCCAGGAAGCCCUACAGUGGUCCAUCUGGGGCCACUGGAGUGGGGAUUUGCUCUUUGGCUCCCCUGACUCACCAAGCACUUGCAGCUUGAUCUUCCAUUCUUGCUCAUUCCCAGUCUUUUUCAACACCCUCAUGAUGUAGGUGCUGUUGUCCUCUUUCUGGACCUUAGAGAUGUACAGUGCGCCACUCUGAGGAUCAAGUCUGACCCUGCCUUUAAAUUUGGAUUCAAAGUACUUAGAUUUUCUGGAAUCCCAUUCUACAAUCUUCUGGUCGAAAGUAUAAAACCAGGUUAGUUGUUUGUAGUUCUCAGGCAGGCUCUCAGAGAUGUUCAGAGUCACGUUGCUGCCGGAGACCACGGUCAUAUGUACCAAGUGACCUGCCAAUGAGAUUCAGAGUGAGACCUGCGCUAGAGGAGGCAGUGUUGCUGACAGGCCCAGGGUAUAGCCUGGGCUGGUGGAACAGGUGAGAAGGAAGGGAUUUCUGCUUAGGAGCAGUGAGUAUGGUUUUCACUGGAGGUCCAGGUCUCCUGCUUAGGAACUCAAGAAAAGUUGAAGCUUGAAAAGUGGGCAUGGGGGAAGGGGAUGCUGCUUAUAAUUAAUCUAGUACUGUCCCCAGAAAAUGAAAGAAUUGAGUAAGGCCAACUGAGGUUGGGCCUGGCUCUCUCCCUUACUCUCAUACCAGUAGACUUUCAAAUAAACUGAUGACAAGUCAUAUCUCUGCUCUGGUCUUGUGUUUCCUGUCUAUUCUCAUUUCAGUAAGCAUGUUGUUAGUCCCUAGAGGCAUAGACAUAAAAAGUACAUGAUUCUGUUUAAAAAUAUUUAAUAUACCAAUGUGGGAGGACAAACACACAAACAAAUAAUCCUAAUAUAUUAUCUUGAUGACUAUAAUAAAGGUAACGUGGGGACCAAGGGAAAGCUUCCCCUUCACCUUCUGAAGGUUUGCCAAAAAUCACUGACAAGAGGCAGAUUAAGGAGGAAAGGCAUACAGAUCAAUUUAACGUGUAAGCAGAGCCUUCCUAAUGAAGAGCCAAAGAUACAGGGCAAAUUGUCCAUUUUUAUGCUUAGGUUCAACAAAGUAUGGACAGUCAUGGAGAAAUAUGAUUGGACAAAAAGGGUAUGAUUGAAUGCCAAUAGACUGACUGCGGGAAACCCAGCAAGGCCUAUCUUUCUAGAUUCUGCUUGGCCUUUCUGUGCCAGAUUCUUUCCUUCCUCCCGUGUGUGGGUCAGGCCCUCUCUAGAAUGGGGGUCUUAUGAUUCACAAUCAAACAAGAUAGGUCAGAUAAUUUCUUUAUAGCUAUUUUUUUUUUACAGAGAAAGGCUCAAGGAAAGUUAGGGUGGUAUAUUUAAAUUUUAUGGCUGGCUUUGGGGAAAAGGGGUUUUGGCUUCUAUGGCCCACCUUGGGAAAGAGGGAUUCCAGUGUCUAUGGCUAGCCUAGGGGAGAAUGGGACUGAUAGACAGGAGGGCAGGAGAAGGUCAGAGAAAAACUUUCACUUCUGAGGCUGCUUCUGAGGCCAUCAUUUUAGGGCAUCAUUUCCUGACUCCUGACAAUAAACACAGUGUGCUAUGGGAAUAUAUUCCUAUCCGGAGGGUAGGGAUAGAAAAUGGAGAAAAUACUAAGAAAAAUCUCUUUGGAGGAGAUGACCACUAGGGUAAGCCAAAGGGUGAUUAAAAGCUAAUAUUUGUUAAGAACUAUCUGUCAGGCACUAUUUGAGACACUUGGGAUACAUCAAUGAACUAAGCAGCUAUCGGGGAAUCUGCCCUGAUAUUCACAUAGGUUCUUUUCUAUUUUUCCUAAGCAUUGGCCAGCUUGAGAAAUAAAGGGACAGAGUACAAAAGAGAGAAAUUUUAAAGCUGAGCAUCUGGGGGAGACAUCACAUGUCGGUAGGUUCCGUGAUGCCCCACAAGCUACAAAAACCAGCAAGUUUUUAUUAGAGAUUUUCAAAAGGGGAGGGAGUGUGCAAAUAGGUGUGGGUGACAGACAUCAAGUACUUAACGGGGUAUUAGAAUACCAUAAGGCAAGAGGAGGCAGGGCGAGAUCACAGGACCACAGGACCGAGGUGAAAUUAAAAUUGCUAAUGAAGUUUCGGGCACCAUUGUCAUUGAUAACAUCUUAUCAGGAGACAGGGUUUUGAGAUCAACCAGUCUGACCAAAAUUUAUUAGGCAGGAGUUUUCUCUUCCUAAUAAGCCUGGGAGUGCUAUGGGAGACUGGAGUCUAUUUCACCUCUGCAGUUUCGACCAUAAGAGACAGGAGCACCUGGGGGUGCUGUUUAUAAGCCUAUACCUCCAGGCGCGUAUUCUCUUUCUCAGGGAUGUUCCAUGCUGAGAAAAAGAACUCAGCGAUAUUUCUCCCAUUUGCUUUUGAAAGAAGAGAAAUAUGGCUCUGUUCUGCCUGGCUCACCGGUGGUCAGAGUUUAAGGUUAUCUCUCUAGUUUCCUAAACAUUGCUGUUAUCUUGUUCUUUUUUCAAGGUGCCCAGAUUUCAUAUUGUUUAAACACACGUGUUCUAUAAUUUGUGCAGUUAAUGCAAUUAUCACAUGGUCCUGAGGUGACAUACAUCCUCCUUGGCUGACAGGAUUAAGAGAUUAAAGUAAAGACAGGCAUAGGAAAUCACAAGGGUAUUGACUGGGGAAGUGAUAAGUGUCCAUGAAAUCUUUACAAUUUAUGUUUAGAGAUUGCAGUAAAGACAGGCAUAAGAAAUUAUGAAAGUAUUAAUUUGGGGAACUAAUAAAUGUCCAUAAAAUAUUCACAAUCCACGUUCUUCUGCCAUGGCUUCAGCCGGUCCCUCCAUUUGGGGUCCCUGACUUCCUGCAACAUCUCUCCCUUUCUUUUUAUAUAAAUGUGCCAUGGCAAUGAAGGCUUGUUCAUUCUCUUGAUUUUGACACAGGAUUCUUUGAGUGGUCUGGGACACUAAAAACAAGCUGAUUAAACACAGAAACAUAUUCCAAAAUUUACUACAGUGGAGCCCCCAGUAGACUUAAUCCAAGUAGUGGGGUUUAAUCCAUAAAGAUUUUCUGCCACCUGAUCUAAUGCCUCAGCUCCAGGCAUGAUGGAUAAGUGAGCUUGAGAGGCUUCAAAAAUUUGUUUCUUUAAUUUAGUUAUGUCCAAUGAUAAAUUAUCUUCUCUACCUAGAAGGUGUCCUUUGACCAUUUCCUAUGAAUGAUCAGUCUCAUUAUAGGAAUACGGGGUGAUGCAGAAAUCUGAAGUAUUCCAAUCGCACUGCAUUUGCAUGUGAUGUUUGAGACUCACUACCUGAUCUCCAAGCCAAAUAACAGACUGUCUUAAAUCAUUAAUUUGACUUGCCAAUUUUUGAUGGAUGCCUUGUUGAGAAUUCCACAUUUGGGUGGAAUUGGCUUGCCAAUCAUUAACAAAAUGAGCCGUUUGAAUAGAUUGAUGUAAUGCCAUUCCAUCAGUGGUGGCCAUUGCAGUGACUGUAAUUAGGCCCGUGAUAACAGCGAUUAAAGUGAAAACAAAUCUCUUAGAUCUUUUUAGAAUUUGCUGUAGCACUUCAUUAAUUAAAUGUAUUGGGGGGAGGAUUCGCAAGGUCUAGGUAAAGUUACUGGAAUCCAGAUUCCUUCUCAAACUCGAACCAACAUUACACUUUUCCUGGAGUCAAAAUGGGAGUUAAUACAAGUGUAUAGAUGACAAUUAAUGCAUUGGAAAGUUUGAUUAUUUGUCCAAAUUUUAAUAUUUCCUACUAACAGCAUGUAAGGAGGCUUAACACAACUCUGUAUGGGAAUAGUCAGGUUGGAGGUAAGUAAAGCAGAAUGUCUGGGUCUAUGUUGAUACUGAGAGAGUGGGACAGUAGUGGGAACAACAGUCAAAAUAGUUUUCCCUUCCCAUACUCGCAGUCCAGACAUGGCAAUAGCCAAUUUCCAAAGUUCUGGGUGUUCUGGGCUCAGAAUGGGGAGUAUCAUACGAGGCUUGGGGGGCGGGUAAUGCCUUUAUCUUCCCAUUUUAAGGGAAAGAAUGAGCUGAUCCUCCUAUGCAAAGUAGAAUGAUGAUUCUCGUUCUCCUGAUAAGAAAUAAAAUAAUUAGCCUCCAGGAAUUCCCUUCCACUAGAGGAGCAAUUAUUUUUUAAAUAGCCCUUUGGUGCCCAGUCUAUUACUAAACCAUAUGAGUCAUUUUUUAAUAUUACUGCAUGUGAGUUAACACAAUCAUCCUAAAUUAAAGUUUUAGAUGGGCCCUCAAAAUUUUUAGGGCAUGGUUUUCCUGCAGGUUUAUAUUGAAAGUAUGGGGUAUCUCCCAUUACUUCUCCUUUCAUUUGUUUUAAAGGAGAAAGGGAGAGGCCAGAGACUAAAUGUCCUAUUUUAUCUGUAGCUGAUGUUUUCGGAAGAUAAGCAGCCUAGAAUUGAGUUUCUAGGUGGAUGCAACCAGGUGCAUGUCCGAGGCACAGAGGGGGGUAUUUAUAAUCUAUGGUAACAUUAAAUGCAGUGCCUUCUUCUCCUGGUUGAGCAGGGCAACGGUCAUCUGUGGCUCUAGGCAUCUACACACUAUCAUUAGUGUAGAUUUCUGCAGGAGCAUCUAUCUAGGUGAGAGGUCGAAUAAGUGGAGGAAAAGGCACAUAAGCCUAAUAAGAAUAAUUAUGUGUAGCAGGUAAAUCAGUGUGAGAGGAAACUGGUGAGACAGAAAGUAUAAGGAGGAGAAUCAUUAAAUAAAACCUAGUGUAAGUGAGAUUGAGUGCUGAAGGAGGAAGAGAAGAACAGAGGGAUGUUAUUUUCAGGCUAAUAGAAAUGGUGAGAUUUUUAGGUUUGUAAGGAGAAAAAGAAAAGUAAUCAGGAGAAGUGGGAUUAGUUAGAUGGGUCUCCACUGCCAUCAGGGAGGAUUGAUUUACACCUAUUGUGAUUUGGUGUGCCUGUUUCUGAGGAGUCAGCAGAGAUCUCACCACGUCUGAAGGCAAUCUCUGACACAGAUGUUUUUUGUCUGUGGUUUUAGUUGUCAGUAUUCACCUGAAGCUUGAGUCUUCUGGUGGGUACCUAGACAUGGGAUUGAUGAUCUCCUGGUGAAACACAAGCAUAUCCUCUUCCCUACGUUAUAAUUGUGCCAGGUUCCUAGGUAUUGGUUUGAGAGUUUUUCCAUAACACUGACUUGCCUUCGUUUAUGGAAAAUUUUUUGCCUGUAUAAUGGCGUUUGGCUGCAGUUACAGUAUUAUCUUUAGGAACAUUUAAAAAAUUUAAAGUAAAUAAUGCCAAAUGUAAUUGGGAGUGUGGAGUAGUUAAAUCAUGUUUUGGUUGUUCAGACUGUUUGGACAAUUGGGUUUUUAAAGUGCGAUUGGCCUGUUCCACCACAGCCUGUCCUUGAGGAUUGUAAGGGAUUCUAGUAAUAUGGGAAAUUCCUUACUGUUGUAUAAAUGAAUCAAAAGCCUUACUAACAUAUCCAGGGGCAUUGUCUGUCUUUAUUUGAUAUGGAAGCCCCAUAACUGCAAAGCAAGAAUACAGAUGUUUUUAAAAAUGGGCCGUGCCUUCCCCUGUUUGUCAAGUAGCCCAGAUAAAACCUGAGAAGGUAUCUACUGAGACAUGCACAUAUGACAGUCUGCCAAAGGAGCUAACAUGAGUCACAUCCAUUUGCCAUCAAGCAUUAGGAGUUAGGCCUCUAGGCUUAACACCAGGUUCCUGAUUUGGAAGUACGAAGACCUGGCACUGAGGGCAGCUGUGAACAAUAAACUUAGCCUGUUUCUAGGUAAGAGCAAAUUUAUCUUUUAAGCCAGUGGCAUUGACAUGAGUGAGAUUAUGGAACUCCUGAGCUUCUUGGGUCAUUAAAGACACCAAACAGUCAACUUCAUGGUUACCAGCAGACAUGGGUCCUGGUAAAGUGGUAUGAGACCUAAUAUGUGUAAUAUAGGAAGGGUGUCUACACUGGUGAACCACCUGUUGUAACCUUGAAAAUAAAGAAGCCAAUUCAGAAUUAUCAAUAUGUUUGAUAGUAGCAGUUUCUAUAUUUUUAGUGGCAUGUACAACAUAAGCGGAAUCUGAGACUGUGGGGAAAAGCAAGAGAGGUCAGAUUGUUACUGUGUCUGUAUAGAAAGAAGUAGACAUAGGAGACUCCAUUUUGUUCUGUACUAAGAAAAAUUAUUCUGCCUUGAGAUGCUGUUAAUCUAUGACCUUACCCCCAACCCCGUGCUCUCUGAAACAUGUGCUGUGUCAAACUCAGGGUUAAAUGGAUUAAGGGCGGUGCAAGAUGUGCUUUGUUAAACAGAUGCUUGAAGGCAGCAUGCUCAUUAAGAGUCAUCACCACUCCCUAAUCUCAAGUACCCAGGGACACAAAAACUGCGGAAGCCUGCAGGGGCCUCUGCCUAGGAAAGCCAGGUAUUGUCCAAGGUUUCUCCCCAUGUGAUAGUCUGAAAUAUGGCCUCGUGGGAAGGGAAAGACCUGACCGUCCCCCAGCCCGACACCCGUAAAGGGUCUGUGCUGAGGAGGAUUAGUAUAAGAGGAAAGCAUGUCUCUUGCAGUUGAGACAAGAGGAAGGCAUCUGUUUCCCGCCCAUCCCUGGGCAAUGGAAUGUCUCGGUAUAAAACCCGAUUGUACGUUCCACCUACUGAGAUAGGGAGAAACCACCUUAGGGCUGGAGGUGGGACAUGCAGGCAGCAAUACUGCUUUGUAAAGCAUUGAGAUGUUUAUGUGUAUGCAUAUCUAAAAGCACAGCAUUUAAUCCUUUACCUUGUCUAUGAUGCAAAGACCUUUGUUCACGUGUUUGUCUGCUCACCCUCUCCCCACUAUUGUCUUGUGACCCUGACACAUCUCCCUCUCGGAGAAACACCCACGAAUGAUCAAUAAAUACUAAGGGGACUCAGAGGCUGGUGGGAUCCUCCAUAUGCUGAACGUUGGUUCCCCGGGCCCCCUUAUUUCUUUCUCUAUACUUUGUCUCUGUGUCUUUUUCUUUUCCAAGUCUCUCAUUGCACCUUACGAGAAACACCCACAGGUGUGGAGGGGCAACCCACCCCUUCAUCUGGUGCCCAACGUGGAGGCUUUUCUCUGGGGUGAAGGUACACUCGAGCGUGGUCAUUGAGGACAAGUCGACAAGAGAUCCCGAGUACAUCUACAGUCAGCCUUACGGUAAGCUUGUGCACUCGGAAGAAGCUAGGGUGACAAUGGGGCAAACUAAAACUAAAAGUAAAUAUGCCUCUUAUCUUAGCUUCAUUAAAAUUCUUUUAAAAAGAGGGGGAGUUAGAGUAUCCACCAAAAAUCUAAUCAAGCUAUUUCAAACAACAGAACAAUUUUGCCCAUGGUUUCCAGAACAAGGAAAUUUAGAUCUAGAAGAUUGGAAAAGAAUUGGUAAGGAACUAAAACAAGCAGGUAGGAAGGGUAAUAUCAUUCCACUUACAGUAUGGAAUGAUUGGCCCAUUAUUAAAGCAGCUUUAGAACCAUUUCAAACAGAAGAUAGCGUUUCAGUUUCUGAUGCCCCUGGAAGCUGUAUAAUAGAUUGUAAUGAAAAGACAAGGAAAAAAUCCCAGAAGGAAACGGAAACUUUACAUUGCGAAUAUGUAGCAGAGCCGUUAAUGGCUCAGUCAACGCAAAAUGUUGACUAUAAUCAAUUACAGGAGGUGAUAUAUCCUGAAACAUUAAAAUUAGAAGGAAAAGGUCCAGAAUUAGUGGGGCCAUUAGAGUCUAAACCACGAGGGCCAAGUCCUCUUUCAGCAGGUCAGGUGACCGUAACAUUACAACCUCAAGCGCAGGUUAGAGAAAAUAAGACCCAACUGCCAGUAGCUUAUCAAUACUGGCCACCGGCCGAACUUCAGUAUCGGCCACCCCCAGAAAGUCAGUAUGGAUAUCUAGGAAUGCCCCCAGCACCACAGGGCAGGGAGCCAUACCCUCAGCCGCCCACUAGGAGACAAUCCUAUGGCACCACCUAGUAGACAGGGUAGUGAAUUACAUGAAAUUAUUGAGAAGUCAAGAAAGGAAGGAGAUACUGAGGCGUGGCAAUUCCCAGUAACGUUAGAACCGAUGCCACCUGGAGAAGGAGCCCAAGAGGGAGAGCCUCUCACAGUUGAGGCCAGAUACAAGUCUUUUUAGAUAAAAAUGCUAAAAGAUAUGAAAGAGGGAGUAAAACAGUAUGGACCCAACUCCCCUUAUAUGAGGACAUUAUUAGAUUCCAUUGCUCAUGGACAUAGACUCAUUCCUUAUGAUUGGGAGAUUCUGGCAAAAUCAUCUCUCUCACCCUCUCAAUUUUUACAAUUUAAGACUUGGUGAAUUGAUGGGGCACAAGAACAGGUCCGAAGAAAUAGGGCUGCCAAUCCUCCAGUUAACAUAGAUGCAGAUCAACUAUUAGGAACAGGUCAAAAUUGGAGCACUAUUAGUCAACAAGCAUUAAUGCAAAAUGAGGCCAUUGAGCAAGUUAGAGCUAUCUGCCUUAGAGCCUGGGAAAAAAUCCAAGACCCAGGAAGCGCCUGCUCCACAUUUAAUACAGUAAGACAAGGUUCAAAAGAGCCCUACCCUGAUUUUGUGGCAAGGCUCCAAGAUGUUGCUCAAAAGUCAAUUGCCAGUGAAAAAGCCCGUAAGGUCAUAGUGGAGUUGAUGGCAUACGAAAACGCCAAUCCUGAGUGUCAAUCAGCCAUUAAGCCAUUAAAAGGAAAGGUUCCCGCAGGAUCAGAUGUAAUCUCAGAGUAUGUAAAAGCCCGUGAUGGAAUUGGAGGAGCUACGCAUAAAGCUAUGCUUAUGGCCCAAGCAAUAACAGGAGUUGUUUUAGGAGGACAAGUUAGAACAUUUGGAGGAAAAUGUUAUAAUUGUGGUCAAAUUGGUCAUUUAAAAAAGAAUUGCCCAGUCUUAAAUAAACAGAAUAUAACUAUUCAAGCUACUACAACAACAGGUAGAGAGCCACCUGACUUAUGUCCAAGAUGUAAAAAAGGAAAACAUUGGGCUAGUCAAUGUCAUUCUAAAUUUGAUAAAAAUGGGCAAUCAUUGUCGGGAAACUACCAAAAGGGCUAGUCAAUGUCGUUCCAAAUUUGAUAAAAAUGGGCAACCAUUGUCGGGAAACUAGCAAAGGGGCCAGCCUCAGGCCCUGCAACAAACUGGGGCAUUCCCAAUUCAGCCCUUUGUUCCUCAGGGUUUUCAGGGACAACAACCCCCACUGUCCCAAGUACCUCAGGGAAUAAGCCAGUUACCACAGUACAACAAUUGUCCCCCGCCACAAGUGGCAGUGCAGCAGUAGAUUUAUGUACUAUACAAGCAGUCUCUCUGCUUCCAGGGGAGCCCCCACAAAAAAUCCCCACAGGAGUAUAUGGCCCGCUGCCUGAGGAGACUGUAGGACUAAUCUUGGGAAGAUCACGUCUAAAUCUAAAAGGAGUUCAAAUUCAUACUGGUGUGGUUGAUUCAGACUAUAAAGGUGAAAUUCAAUUGGUUAUUAGCUCUUCAAUUCCUUGGAGUGCCAGUCCAGGAGACAGGAUUGCUCGAUUAUUACUCCUGCCAUAUAUUAAGGUUGGAAAUAGUGAAAUAAAAAGAACAGGAGGGUUUGGAAGCACUGAUCCGACAGGAAAGGCUGCAUAUUGGGCAAGUCAGGUCUCAGAGAACAGACCUGUGUGUAAGGCCGUUAUUCAAGGAAAACAGCUUGAAGGAUUGGUAGACACUGGAGCAGAUGUCUCUAUCAUUGCUUUAAAUCAGUGGCCAAAAAAUUGGCCUAAACAAAAGACUGUUACAGGACUUGUCGGCAUAGUCACAGCCUCAGAAGUGUAUCAGAGUACUGAGAUUUUACAUUGCUUAGGGCCACAUAAUCAAGAAAGUACUGUUCAGCCAAUGAUCACUUCAAUUCCUCUUAAUCUGUGGGGUCGAGAUUUGUUACAACAAUGGGGUGCGGAAAUCACCAUGACCGCUACAUUAUAUAGCCCCAUGAGUCAAAAAAUCAUGACCAAGAUGGGAUAUAUACCAGGAAAGGGACUAGGAAAAAAUGAAGAUGGCAUUAAAGUUCCAAUUGAGGCUAAAAUAAAUCACGGAAGAGAAGGAACAGGGUAUCCUUUUUAGGGGUGACCACUGUAGAGCCUCCUAAACCCAUACCGUUAACUUGGAAAACAGAAAAACUGGUGUGGGUAAAUCAGUGGCCGCUACCAAAACAAAAACUGGAGGCUUUACAUUUAUUAGCAAAUGAACAGUUAGAAAAGGGACAUAUUGAGCCUUCAUUCUCGCCUUGGAAUUCUCCUGUGUUUGUAAUUCAGAAGAAAUCCAGCAAAUGGCGUAUGUUAACUGACUUAAGGGCUGUAAAUGCCGUAAUUCAACCCAUGGGGCCUCUCCAACCUGGGUUGCCCUCUCCAGCCAUGAUCCCAAAAGAUUGGCCUUUAAUUAUAAUUGAUCUAAAGGACUGCUUUUUUACCAUCCCUCUGGCAGAGCAGGAUUGUGAAAAAUUUGCCUUUACUAUACCAGCCAUAAAUAAUAAAGAACCAGCCACCAGGUUUCAGUGGAAAGUGUUACCUCAGGGAAUGCUUAAUAGUCCAACUAUUUGUCAGACUUUUGUAGGUCGAGCUCUUCAACCAGUUAGAGACAAGUUUUCAGACUGUUAUAUUAUUCAUUAUUUUGAUGAUAUUUUAUGUGCUGCAGAAACGAAAGAUAAAUUAAUUGACUGUUAUACAUUUCUGCAAGCAGAGGUUGCCAAUGCAGGACUGGCAAUAGCAUCUGAUAAGAUCCAAACCUCUACUCCUUUUCAUUAUUUAGGGAUGCAGAUAGAAAAUAGAAAAAUUAAGCCACAAAAAAUAGAAAUAAGAAAAGACACAUUAAAAACACUAAAUGAUUUUCAAAAAUUGCUGGGAGAUAUUAAUUGGAUUCGGCCAACUCUAGGCAUUCCUACUUAUGCCAUGUCAAAUUUGUUCUCUAUCUUAAGAGGAGACUCAGACUUAAAUAGUAAAAGAAUGUUAACCCCAGAGGCAACAAAAGAAAUUAAAUUAGUGGAAGAAAAAAUUCAGUCAGCGCAAAUAAAUAGAAUAGAUCCCUUAGCCCCACUCCAACUUUUGAUUUUUGCCACUGCACAUUCUCCAACAGGCAUCAUUAUUCAAAAUACUGAUCUUGUGGAGUGGUCAUUCCUUCCUCACAGUACAGUUAAGACUUUUACAUUGUACUUGGAUCAAAUAGCUACUUUAAUUGGUCCGACAAGAUUACGAAUAAUAAAAUUAUGUGGAAAUGACCCAGACAAAAUAGUUGUCCCUUUAACCAAGGAACAAGUUAGACAAGCCUUUAUCAAUUCUGGUGCAUGGCAGAUUGGUCUUGCUAAUUUUGUGGGAAUUAUUGAUAAUCAUUACCCAAAAACAAAAAUCUUCCAGUUCUUAAAAUUGACUACUUGGAUUCUACCUAAAAUUACCAGAUGUGAACCUUUAGAAAAUGCUCUAACAGUAUUUACUGAUGGUUCCAGCAAUGGAAAAGUGGCUUACACAGGGCCAAAAGAACGAGUAAUCAAAACUCCAUAUCAAUCGGCUCAAAGAGCAGAGUUGGUUGCAGUCAUUACAGUGUUACAAGAUUUUGAUCAACCUAUCAAUAUUAUAUCAGAUUCUGCAUAUGUAGUACAGGCUACAAGGGAUGUUGAGACAGCUCUAAUUAAAUAUAGCAUGGACGAUCAGUUAAACCAGCUAUUCAAUUUAUUACAACAAACUGUAAGAAAAAGAAACUUCCCAUUUUAUAUUACUCAUAUUCGAGCACACACUAAUUUACCAGGGCCUUUGACUAAAGCAAAUGAACAAGCUGACUUACUGGUAUCAUCUGCAUUCAUAAAAGCACAAGAACUUCAUGCUUUGACUCAUGUAAAUGCAGCAGGAUUAAAAAACAAAUUUGAUGUCACAUAGAAACAGGCAAAAGAUAUUGUACAACAUUGCACCCAGUGUCAAGUCUUAGACCUGCCCACUCAAGAGGCAGGAGUUAACCCAGAGGUCUGUGUCCUAAUGCAUUAUGGCAAAUGGAUGUCACGCAUGUACCUUCAUUUGGAAGAUUAUCAUAUGUCAUGUAACAGUUGAUACUUAUUCACAUUUCAUGUGGGCAACUUGCCAAACAGGAGAAAGUACUUCCCAUGUUAAAAAACAUUUAUUGUCUUGUUUUGCUGUAAUGGGAGUUCCAGAAAAAAUCAAAACUGACAAUGGACCAGGAUAUUGUAGUAAAGCUUUCCAAAAAUUCUUAAGUCAGUGGAAAAUUUCACAUACAACAGGAAUUCCUUAUAAUUCCCAAGGACAGGCCAUAGUUGAAAGAACUAAUAGAACACUCAAAACUCAAUUAGUUAAACAAAAAGAAGGGGGAGACAGUAAGGAGUGUACCACUCCUCAGAUGCAACUUAAUCUAGCACUCUAUACUUUAAAUUUUUUAAACAUUUAUAGAAAUCAGACUACUACUUCUGCAGAACAUCUUACUGGUAAAAAGAACAGCCCACAUGAAGGAAAACUAAUUUAGUGGAAAGAUAAUUAAAAUAAGACAUGGGAAAUAGGGAAGCUGAUAACGUGGGGGAGAGGUUUUGCUUGUGUUUCACCAGGAGAAAAUCAGCUUCCUGUUUGGAUACCCACUAGACAUUUGAAGUUCUACAAUGAACCCAUCAGAGAUGCAAAGAAAAGCGCCUCCACGGAGAUGGUAACACCAGUCACAUGGAUGGAUAAUCCUAUAGAAGUAUAUGUUAAUGAUAGUGUAUGGGUACCUGGCCCCACAGAUGAUCGCUGCCCUGCCAAACCUGAGGAAGAAGGGAUGAUGAUAAAUAUUUCCAUUGGGUAUCAUUAUCCUCCUAUUUGCCUAGGGAGAGCACCAGGAUGUUUAAUGCCUGCAGUCCAAAAUUGGUUGGUAGAAGUACCUACUGUCAGUCCUAACAGUAGAUUCACUUAUCACAUGGUAAGCGGGAUGUCACUCAGGCCACGGGUAAAUUAUUUACAAGACUUUUCUUAUCAAAGAUCAUUAAAAUUUAGACCUAAAGGGAAAACUUGCCCCAAGGAAAUUCCUAAAGGAUCAAAGAAUACAGAAGUUUUAGUUUGGGAAGAAUGUGUGGCCAAUAGUGUGGUGAUAUUACAAAACAAUGAAUUCGAAACUAUUAUAGAUUGGGCACCUCGAGGUCAAUUCUACCACAAUUGCUCAGGACAAACUCAGUCGUGUCCAAGUGCACAAGUGAGUCCAGCUGUUGAUAGCGACUUAACAGAAAGUCUAGACAAACAUAAGCAUAAAAAAUUACAGUCUUUCUACCUUUGGGAAUGGGAAGAAAAAGGAAUCUCUACCCCAAGACCAAAAAUAAUAAGUCCUGUUUCUGGUCCUGAACAUCCAGAAUUGUGGAGGCUUACUGUGGCCUCACACCACAUUAGAAUUUGGUCUGGAAAUCAAACUUUAGAAACAAGAUAUCGUAAGCCAUUUUAUACUAUCGACCUAAAUUCCAUUCUAACGGUUCCUUUACAAAGUUGCAUAAAGCCCCCUUAUAUGCUAGUUGUAGGAAAUAUAGUUAUUAAACCAGCCUCCCAAACUAUAACCUGUGAAAAUUGUAGAUUGUUUACUUGCAUUGAUUCAACUUUUAAUUGGCAGCACCGUAUUCUGCUGGUGAGAGCAAGAGAAGGCAUGUGGAUCCCUGUGUCCACGGACCGACCGUGGGAGGCCUCGCCAUCCAUCCAUAUUUUGACUGAAAUAUUAAAAGGCAUUUUAAAUAGAUCCAAAAGAUUCAUUUUUACUUUAAUUGCAGUGAUUAUGGGAUUAAUUGCAGUCACAGCUACGGCUGCUGUGGCAGGAGUUGCAUUGCACUCUUCUGUUCAGUCAGUAAACUUUGUUAAUUAUUGGCAAAAGAAUUCUACAAGAUUGUGGAAUUCACAAUCUAGUAUUGAUCAAAAAUUGGCAAGUCAAAUUAAUGAUCUUAGACAAACUGUCAUUUGGAUGGGAGACAGGCUCAUGACCUUAGAACAUCAUUUCCAGUUACAGUGUGACUGGAAUACGUCAGAUUUUUGUAUUACACCCCAAAUUUAUAAUGAGUCUGAGCAUCACUGGGACAUGGUUAGACGCCAUCUACAGGGAAGAGAAGAUAAUCUCACUUUAGACAUUUCCAAAUUAAAAGAACAAAUUUUCGAAGCAUCAAAAGCCCAUUUAAAUUUGGUGCCAGGAACUGAGGCAAUUGCAGGAGUUGCUGAUGGCCUCGCAAAUCUUAACCCUGUCACUUGGAUUAAGACCAUCAGAAGUACUAUGAUUAUAAAUCUCAUAUUAAUCAUUGUGUGCCUGUUUUGUCUGUUGUUAGUCUGCAGGUGUACCCAACAGCUCCGAAGAGACAGUGACAUCGAGAACGGGCCAUGAUGACGAUGGCGGUUUUGUCGAAAAGAAAAGGGGGAAAUGUGGGGAAAAGCAAGAGAGAUGAGAUUGUUACUGUGUCUGUAUAGAAAGAAGUAGACAUAGGAGACUCCAUUUUGUUCUGUACUAAGAAAAAUUCUUCUGCCUUGAGAUGCUGUUAAUCUAUGACCUUACCCCCAACCCCGUGCUCUCUGAAACAUGUGCUGUGUCAAACUCAGGGUUAAAUGGAUUAAGGGCGGUGCAAGAUGUGCUUUGUUAAACAGAUGCUUGAAGGCAGCAUGCUCAUUAAGAGUCAUCACCACUCCCUAAUCUCAAGUACCCAGGGACACAAACACUGCGAAAGACCGCAGGGACCUCUGCCUAGGAAAGCUAGGUAUUGUCCAAGGUUUCUCCCCAUGUGAUAGUCUGAAAUAUGGCCUCGUGGGAAGGGAAAGACCUGACCAUCCCCCAGACCAACACCCGUAAAGGGUCUGUGCUGAGGAGGAUUAGUAUAAGAGGAAAGCAUGCCUCUUGCAGUUGAGAGAAGAGGAAGACAUCUGUCUCCUGCCCAUCCCUGGGCAAUGGAAUGUCUCAGUAUAAAACCCGAUUGAACAUUCCAUCUACUGAGAUAGGGAAAAACUGCCUUAGGGCUGGAGGUGGGACAUGUGGGCAGCAAUACUGCUUUGUAAAGCAUUGAGAUGUUUAUGUGUAUGCAUAUCUAAAAGCACAGCACUUGAUCCUUUACCUUGUCUAUGAUGCAAAGACCUUUGUUCACGUGUUUGUCUGCUCACCCUCUCCCCACUAUUGUCUUGUGACCCUGACACAUCCCCCUCUCGGAGAAACACCCACGAAUGAUCAAUAAAUACUAAGGGAACUCAGAGGCUGGCGGGAUCCUCCAUAUGCUGAACGUUGGUUCCCCGGGCCCCCUUAUUUCUUUCUCUAUACUUUGUCUCUGUGUCUUUUUCUUUUCCAAGUCUCUCGUUCCACCUUAUGAGAAACACCCACAGGUGUGGAGGGGCAACCCACCCCUUCAUGAGACAAUAUUUAAAGGUUUGGGGAAAUCCUGUAAGGCAGUAAUCACAGCAAUUAACUCCGCCUUUUGAGCAGAAGUAUAAGAGGUAGAAAUAAGUUUGUCUGUAGGACUUACAUAGCCAGCAUUGCCAUUACUGGAGCCAUCAGUGAACACUGUAACGGCCUCAGGAAUGGGUUGAUUUUUGGUUAAUCGAGGAACCACCUAAGAAGUCAUUUUUAUAAAAUCAAAUAAUUUGUUUUUUGGAUAAUGAUUGUCAAUAACGCCAAUAAAAUCAGCCAAGUGAAUUUGCCACAGUACAGAAUGUUGAAAGGCAGCUUGAACUUUGAGCCAAUUUAAAGGAACUACAAUUAUAUUUGGAUCAAAUCCAGAAAUUUGAAGUAUUCUGCACCAAGCCUGUCUAAUUAAUAUGGCUAUUUGGUCUAGAUAAACAGACAAAGUUUUUGAGACAGAAUAAGGAAGAAAACAUCACUCCACUAAAUCAUUAUGUUGAACUAUUAGUCCAGUAGGGGAGUGUAAUGAAGCAAAAACUAGAAGCUGAAAAGGCUGAAAUGGCUGUACUCUAGAUAACUGGGCAGUCUGGAUUCUUUCUUCUACAAAUUCCAGUUCUAUUAAAGCCUCAGAGGUCAAAAUCCUGGCGCUGUGGAGAUUGGAAUCUCCCCGCAACAUAGAAAUCAAGUUAGACAGUGCAUAGGUUGGAAUGCCUAAAGUAGGUCUUAAAUAAUUAAUGUUACCUAAAAGUUUGUGGAAGUCAUCUAAAGUUUUUAAAGAAUCUCUCCUAAUUUGAACUUUUUGAGGUUGAAUACAUUGUUUAUCGACCACCAUUCCUAAAUAUUGAACAGGAGUGGUCUGAUGAAUUUUAUCUUGAGCAAUGUGUAAUCCAGCCUCUAUAACACAGCAGCUCAAAAUUUGGUAACAGUCAAUUCUUUAUCAGUGGGGGCAGCAAUUAAAAUAUCAUCAAUAUAAUGAUGAAUAUAGGCCUCGGGAAAUUGGGCUUGAACUGGUGAAAGCACUUGCCCAACAUAAAGCUGGCAGAUUGUAGGGCUAUUUAGCAUUCCUUGAGGAAGUACUUUCCAUUGAUAAUGAACUGCAGGUUCCUGAUUAUUGAUAGAUGGUACAGUAAAAGCAAAUUUUUCACAAUCUGAUUUAUGUAAAGCAAUAUAAAAAAAAAUCUUUAAGAUCAAUAACUAUGAGAGGCUAAUUUUUAGGUAUUAAAGCCAGGUUGGACGGCCCCCAUAGGUUUAAUUACAGCAUUAAUGGCCCUUAAAUCGGUUACCAUCCGCCAUUUGCCUGAUUUCUUUUUUACUAGGAACACAGGAGAAUUCUAAGGGGAAAGAGAAUGUUCCACAUAUCCAAGUUGCAACUGCUCAGAAACCAAUUGAUUUAAAGCCUCCAGUUUUUCUUUAGAAAGCGGCCACUGCUGAACCUAAACGGGAGUUUUAGGUUUCCAUUGUAAGGGAAUGGGAUCAGGAGGUAUGGCAGUGGCUGCCACUAAAAAGAAUAACCUAAACCAGCCCUGUUUUCUUUUAUAGUGACUGGGAGGGGUUUGGUAAUCCAGGAACAAACCUUAUAUUUUCCAUCAUAUGCUGACUGGGAGCACUAGAAGAGUUAUGUGGAAUAUUAAUUUCAGCCCUCUAUUUUGCCAGUAAAUCUCUACCCCAAAGAUUAAUGUGAAUUGGCAUGAUAUAGGGCUGAAUUGUACCUUUUUGACCAUCAGGGCCAGUGCAAAGCAAGAUAAAUGUGCUCUGAUAAAUUUCCUCGGCCUUUCCAACACCUACUAGUCCUACCUUAGUGGGAUGUUUAAGCCAAGAGGAAGGCCAUAAACUAGAGGAAAUAACAGAAACUUCGGCACCAGUAUCUACUAGGCCCUCAAACUUUUUUCCUUGAAUGUGUAUGAUGCAGGUGGGCCGUUGUUUAGAAAUUACAUUAAUCCAGUAAGUGGCCUUUUCACCGCCGGAGCCUAUCCCAGGGCCACAUGUCUUAUCGCCUUUGUUUAAAAUGAUAUUAGGUAGUAAAAGCAGUUGAGCAACUGACUCACCAGACGCAAUGGAAAUAGGAAACUUGGCAGACACAAUUAAUUUAAUCUCAUCAACAGAAUCAGAAUUAAUGAGACCAGUAUGAAUGGUGAAUCCUUUAGCAGAGGUGGAUGCUCUACCUAACACCAGGCCCACUGAACCUUGAGGUAAAGGGCCAGUGACCCCCGUGGGGACAAUCAAAGGCAAAGAAUCAGGAAGUAAAUUUAGAGGAAUAGUACUAAAGAGAUCAACCACCCCGCCUCCUACUGUGGAGGAGGACAAGCAUUGUACUGAGACAGAAGUAGAGGCUGGGACCUAUUUGGUUUGGUUGUAGGUAGAUUUGUUUGUGCUGGGGGUUGCACUGGGACUGCCUGAAGUGGAAACGCAAUGUUGGUCUGAGUUUGAAGUGUCCUAUUUGAUGUCGGGUCCAUCCCAGGCCCCGCUCCCUGUUUCCCUGGUGUUGUGGUAGGGGGUUUCCAUCUACAUUAUACCUAGAGCGGCAAACAUUUGCCCAAUGUUUACCUUUGCGACAACGUGGGCAAACAGUAGGAGCAGCAUUUGGCCAUGUUUGUUGAACCGACUUGGCCGCUUGUAAGUUUUUAACAGUGCAACUUUUUUGAAUAUGACCAAGUUGGCCACAAUUAUAGCAGGCUCCAAGAGAAGAAUUAAUGGGACCAGUUUGGUUGGUGUCCUUCAUGGCCGGUGCCCACAGAAUAGCUUUGUGGGUAUCUGAUCCAAUGCCUUCACAAGCUUUAAUAUAUGCAGGCAACACCUCGUGAUCAGGUAAAUUUUGCGUUGGACAGAAUGCAUGGCCAUUUUACAUUCAUGGUUUGCAUUUUCAAAAGCUAACAUAUAAAGGAGAAUGCCUUGAGUGCGCUCAUCAGAGACAGAUUUUUGAACAGCAUCUUGUAAUUUAGCCAAAAAAUCUGGGUAUAAUUCAGAGUGACUUUGUUUAACUAUGGUAAAAGGAACAGGAGCUUGGCCUGGAGCGUGUAAUUUAUCCCAAGCUCUCAUACACACCUUUGUUACUUGUUCUGUGGUAAGGGCAUCAAAGUUUAACUGGGCAUAAGCAUCAGAGAAACUAUCGGAGCCUGUGAGCUGAGCCUGAGUAAUUAGAAUGCCAUUACUGCUAUUUAGCUGAGCCUGCAAAUGGGCCUCUUCUGACCACCAGGUAUGGAAUACGGAAUUGUAAAUGCUGAGAUGGGGUUAGAACAGCUUUUGCCAAAAGGUCCCAAUCUAAGGGAAGUAAGUGACUUCAGUACGAAAAGUUUGUAAAACCAUCUUAACAUAAGGAGAAGUAGGACCAUACUGAGUACAAGCAUCCCUAAAUUCUUUUAAAAAAGGUAAGAUUGAACAGCGCAUAUCGAUGCAGACCGGUUUAGGACCCGAAACGACAGGAGGGUGAGGGGCUGUAGUGGAUGGGGGAUGGCCUGGAGAAUGAUAGGUAAAGUGUAGUUUGGUCCUGGAGCCAUUAGCUGAUGCUGGAGGUUUGAAGAGAGAAGAAUUAGCAUAUCUAUGGUACAUGCAGCAAAGAUCCCUACCUUAACAGAGCUUGCAUUAGAGUGGGGUGAAAAAACGUAAGCAAUCAACACACUAACAGAACACACUGUAUAGUAUGUAAGGAGAUGAUAACUGCCAUGACAGAGGAGAAAACCUAGAAUAAGGUAAGGGGAGUCACAAGUACUGGUAGGGGCAAAAGGGUGAACUUCAUUUAUAAGGUGAUAAGUAGGUCACAUCUGAGUAAAGACUUGGAGGAGAGAGGUGGCCAAGAGGGUAUCUGGGGUAGGAGGGACCCAGACAGAGGAAAGAGCCAGAGCAAAGGCCCUGGGGCAGGGAUUUGCCUGCCAUACAUAAACAACAGCAAGGAGGUGGCGAGUGGGUAGUGUGGAGUGAACAAGGGGAUUGGGUGUUGAGAGACACAGUCAGAGAGGGAGUGAGAUUGGAGAGAGUAGAUACAUUUUAGCUUUAUUAAUAAUGUCUUGUCCUGUAAAAAAAAAAUGCUUUCCUGUAAAAGUGGCUCAUGUCUUGUGUGUGCAUUUACAAUGUAUUUAGAAGCAAGUUAUUAGAAGGUAACAAAGUGGAGACUGUAUAAACCAUUGUUUCACAAAGUUUGGAUCAGAGGCAGAUUUCCCGUGAAAGUGAUGAAGCUGAAGCUUCAGGGCUUCUUGGAUGGCCCUGGAGGAGCCCUAGCAGUAUUCAUGUAAUCCAUUUUACAAAACAUAUCUUAAACAUUAAUUAGACCACAGCCUCUGUCUACUCUAACAUCCCCUUCAUCACAUUUCUGUUUUUGUUGGGUGGCAUCUCAGUUAUGGGCAUUUUGAGGUCUGGCCAAGGGGAAGUAGAAAUGGGAAGUACUUAGUUGGGGUUAGCGGGAUACAUGUAUGAGGGUUGCAAACUCUUGUGUGUGAAGUUCCCGCUACCCACUUCAGUGAAGAAAUGGCAUCCAGGAAUAUUCUUGCUGCCCUCUGCACUGACUCACUGGCAAUGGCCAUGGACAUGUUGCAAUCGGGCUGCAGGUGGGAAGCAGAGGAGAAAGCAGGUUGGAAGUGAACAACAGCCAGAGCUAUUCAGUAGCAAAGUAUUGUGGAAGCACGAAGGCAUUUAAUUAACUAAAAUUAUGCUGCUAUUUUUUAUGCUGUCAUGUUCUUUGUAGUAUUUGUAUUUUUUUAACCUGAACUAAUUCCCUGGGAUUUCUUUUUUUUUAUUCUAAUUGAAUUUAUUUUUGUUCCUAUUUGUAUUUCCAGUUUUGUUCUUUUAUUAUUUUUCUUUUUCAUGAGAAUACUCCAAAUUAUAUAAGCCUCAGGUCAUUUUUAAAAACCUGGUUUGGUUAAGAUAAGGAGAAAGAAAAGAUGAUAAGGACAAAGUACAAGAUGAAGGGAGGUCCAUUGGUCCUUUUUGUGGAGGGAGAACUUAGAAUAUGUAUACAAAGGCUAAACAAGAGCUGUGGAAUAAAAGCUAAAGGUAGAAGAAGAGGAAAUAUGUCCUAUAUCACUCUGGUGUCAUAUGCUGCCGCACAAAAACUCAGUUGUACUCUUCAACAUGAUAUAUACUAGCUGUUCACUUUCCACAUAUCCAUCAUUUCCAAAAACAUUCUCAACCACUAAAAGAUAAAAAUGUCUGUGACCCCAGGGCUUUCAAGUUCCUGUUCAUUCAGCCUUCCAACCAUUCAUCCAUCUAUUCAACAAAUGUUUAUUAAGCACUUACCCUGUCCUGGUUUGUACACGGAAAUACCUAGGCAUUCAUUUCUACAGUGCUUCUGAUUGGUCCAGCCCAUGCCCUAUAAUCCCUCUGACAGAAUAAGUUCAACCCUCAUACAUGUAUCCCACUAAC